GAGUGGCCCCUCAGGUCUGUUUUGGGGACAUUCACCCAGACCCCAGCUAAUGCGCGCCCCUUCCCCUAAACCAUUUAGUCUUGGAAGCUGACUCUGCCCUCUGGGACCUUUUCUUCCAGGCCACUCCUUGCUCAGACUCCAGUCUCAGGUGGGAUGGUCCUCAGAACCGUGUGAUGUGACGGUGGGGCCUGUCCCAAAAUACAAACCCCAAUGCCCAGUUUCCAGUCCUCUUGGAAGCAUGGGCAGGACAGGACUUAGGCUAGGCUGGAGGGGUGGUUUCUUUUGACCUCUGUGGGGUCUAUUAAUAUUUGGGAGCACUGCCUGGGAUCUGGGGUGAUAGGCAUCUGGGGAUGGUAAUCCUGUCCCUGCGACAAAUAAGCGGGGUAAUCUCCGCUUGCUCAGUACCCACACCCAUCUUGUGUCGGUAGUUUUGGGAGUGUGGGAAGCUGGCAGGGCCCCUGGCAAGAUGACCAGUGUUGUCUUGACUUACUGGGUUUUGGGAAAGGAGUAUGGCAACUGAUACCCCGGCUCCCAGGGCUUUGGCUGAACAUUCUCUCUGACGCCUGCUGUCUUUCCUCCCUCUACUCCCCUCUCCACCCUCUGGCUGCUGUCUGGAGCCCACACAGUUUGUGGGGGGAUGCACGGUGGGGGGCAGGGCCUGGAUCUCCGUGUGUGUCCAGGGAGUAUUCUGGGAAUUGGCAGGAUUGGCUGAGGGUGUCUUGGUGUCCCCGCAGGGUGGGCGGCAUGUGGGGACCUAGUGUGAGAAUGUGUCAGCGUUGGUGUGUCUGUCCCCAGUCUGGCUCGGGUGUGGGUGUCUCGGGUGUGGGUGUCUCUUGCUUCGUCUGGAUCUUGCCUCCCGCUCCAGUCCCGCCCUCCCCUCGCUCCCCCCUAGCUGGGACCGCCUGCUUGCUUUCCCUCUCUCCCCACAACUGGAGCCUCCCUUGCCUGUUCCUGGAAUUUGGAGAGGAGGAGGAGGAGGAAGAGGCAGGCAGACAGACCUCCCACACUCUAGCCCGCCCACCUGGCAUCAUGGGGAAAUGAAAUAGGUGCUAUGGAACUACAUUUUCCCUGGCUUCCCUAGACCCUCCAGCACACAUCAUGAGGGCCAGGGGCCAGCUCUUAUGGAAAGGCCAUGGGCUGUCCAUCCCUCUGGCCAGUGACACCUCCUUCUACUUAACAUCCUGCCCCAAAGGGCCCCUGCUGGACCUCCAGGCACCACUGUCAGCCUGGGGAGCCGGUGGGGGGAUUAGGCUGCUGCCAGGCUGGCCCGCACCUGUUGCCAACCCCAGCCCUAUAACUGGAGCUUGCUAGGGAGGGGGCUGCAGAAUGACAGGUGUAAUUUCUGCAGCUAGGCAACUCCACCCCCCCAACUGGAUAUGCCUUUCCCUUCUGCCGGAACAAGGGAAGACUUCCCCUUCGCCACUCCAAGUGUCAACCUGAUCUUAUGGAUGAUGCCCCUGUCCUGCCUGAUGACCCCCACCCCCAUCCCUGGCUGCAGAGCUGGGCUGCCCUCCUUCAAGUUUUCAGAGCUGUGCUGCCCUGGCAGGGCUAGGGGUGUGGGGGUGUGUAGAUGGGGGUGGUUCUCUGUUAAUGUUUUAAUUGCCUAAAAACUGGGAGCUCAGCUCUGGGCCAGUGGGGAGUCUGGGUCUGGCUGGCCGCCCGGUUUGGGCUAAAUAUAGUCUGGGACAUCUGCAGAGAAGGGGAGGGGGGUGGAGGGAGGUUCCAUUCCCCCACCUUCAGCCAAGGUGCCCUCGUCUGGGCGGGCACCUUGGAGCAGUGAGGGGGAUUCCUCAAGCACAAAAGGCAGGGGAGAAGUGGCAGGGAAGAGGUGGCAGGGGAGAGGUGGCAGGGGCUAGGCACAGUUGGGACCUUGCUUGCCUGGAGGCCAGUAGAUGCCGGAGAUGAACCUGGAGGCUCAGGACAGGGCAAGAGUGGGGCACGCCGGGGCUGGGUCCUCUGGCUGUUCCCUCUCCCCACAGAGUUACUUGAGGUCAGGCAGUCUCCAUGUGUCACUGUACCCCGCAGGCAGUGUCACCGUGACCCACUCGCUGUGUGUCUGUGUGUACACACCUACCUUGGAGUGGCUUUAUCCCGGCCCUCCCCCCGGAGCCUCUGUCCCCUGGGUCCUACCGCAGGUCCUCAGCCCUCCUUCCCUCUGUCCCUCGCCCUACAGUGAAACCUUCAGCCCAGGAAUCGAGACUUGAGAAGGGGAAGCUGCGGUGGGGAGUUCUCUGAUCUCCAGUCACGGCAGGAAGUGGAAAAGAGGGGGGUUAAGGGGGGGACCCAUGAGUGGCAGGCAGGGAGGGAGAGCCCUGUCAGUCCUGUGACCCACUGUGCAGAUCAAGGAGGGGUUGGCCCCCUUCCUAGUGGUCCCCCUUCCCUCCAGCUCCAGGUAGGAGAAACCUGGGGGACAGCUGAUUCCCCAGGGGGUGCAAACAAUCUUCAUCACCCCCCCAACACUAAGAAAAAAAAUGUCUUCCUGUCACGUGGCUGUCACUUCCUGUCCCACUGUGGUUCCUGGGAUGUUUGUUGUUGGUUGCCAUGGUGAUGUCUGCCGUGGGCACUACCCCUGGUUCUUGUGGGGAAGGAGCUACCCCUCCCCACCAGGCUGGGGGGGUACUUGGGGGACUUGACUAGGGGGUCCUUUCAGGCUGAGUGUGUGUGGUCUCUGAUGCCCCAGAUUCCCCAGGACCCCCCAGACUUCUGUCUGUGGGGAGGAGUCACUGCCACCUACUCAGACUGAGUGCUGGGGAGACUGUGACCGCAUCUGGCUGUGCCUGACCGUGGCUGUGACUUUGUGUGUGACUCUGGGGUGUAACGCGUGGGCAGCUAGGGAUGCUGAUGCUGGAGAAGGGAUCCUGGCACCUUCUGAGGCAUCACAGGACAUGGCCCCCUCAGCCACCUAGCUGGGGCCCAUCUAGGAGUGGCAUCUUUUUUGGUGCCCUGAAGGCCAGCUCUGGACCUUCCCAGGAAAAGUGCCAGCUCACAGAACUGCUUGACCAAAGGACCGGCUCUUGAGACAUCCCCCAACCCACCUGGCCCCCAGCUAGGGUGGGGGCUCCAGGAGACUGAGAUUAGCCUGCCCUCUUUGGACAGCAGCUCCAGGACAGGGCGGGUGGGCUGACCACCCAAACCCCAUCUGGGCCCAGGCCCCAUGCCCCGAGGAGGGGUGGUCUGAAGCCCACCAGAGCCCCCUGCCAGACUGUCUGCCUCCCUUCUGACUGUGGCCGCUUGGCAUGGCCAGCAACAGCAGCUCCUGCCCGACACCUGGGGGCGGGCACCUCAAUGGGUACCCGGUGCCUCCCUACGCCUUCUUCUUCCCCCCUAUGCUGGGUGGACUCUCCCCGCCAGGCGCUCUGACCACUCUCCAGCACCAGCUUCCAGUUAGUGGAUAUAGCACACCAUCCCCAGCCACCAUUGAGACCCAGAGCAGCAGUUCUGAAGAGAUAGUGCCCAGCCCUCCCUCGCCACCCCCUCUACCCCGCAUCUACAAGCCUUGCUUUGUCUGUCAGGACAAGUCCUCAGGCUACCACUAUGGGGUCAGCGCCUGUGAGGGCUGCAAGGGCUUCUUCCGCCGCAGCAUCCAGAAGAACAUGGUGUACACGUGUCACCGGGACAAGAACUGCAUCAUCAACAAGGUGACCCGGAACCGCUGCCAGUACUGCCGACUGCAGAAGUGCUUUGAAGUGGGCAUGUCCAAGGAGUCUGUGAGAAACGACCGAAACAAGAAGAAGAAGGAGGUGCCCAAGCCCGAGUGCUCUGAGAGCUACACGCUGACGCCGGAGGUGGGGGAGCUCAUUGAGAAGGUGCGCAAAGCGCACCAGGAAACCUUCCCUGCCCUCUGCCAGCUGGGCAAAUACACUACGAACAACAGCUCAGAACAACGUGUCUCUCUGGACAUUGACCUCUGGGACAAGUUCAGUGAACUCUCCACCAAGUGCAUCAUUAAGACUGUGGAGUUCGCCAAGCAGCUGCCCGGCUUCACCACCCUCACCAUCGCCGACCAGAUCACCCUCCUCAAGGCUGCCUGCCUGGACAUCCUGAUCCUGCGGAUCUGCACGCGGUACACGCCCGAGCAGGACACCAUGACCUUCUCGGACGGGCUGACCCUGAACCGGACCCAGAUGCACAACGCUGGCUUCGGCCCCCUCACCGACCUGGUCUUUGCCUUCGCCAACCAGCUGCUGCCCCUGGAGAUGGAUGAUGCGGAGACGGGGCUGCUCAGCGCCAUCUGCCUCAUCUGCGGAGACCGCCAGGACCUGGAGCAGCCGGACCGGGUGGACAUGCUGCAGGAGCCGCUGCUGGAGGCGCUAAAGGUCUACGUGCGGAAGCGGAGGCCCAGCCGCCCCCACAUGUUCCCCAAGAUGCUAAUGAAGAUUACUGACCUGCGAAGCAUCAGCGCCAAGGGGGCUGAGCGGGUGAUCACGCUGAAGAUGGAGAUCCCGGGCUCCAUGCCGCCUCUCAUCCAGGAAAUGUUGGAGAACUCAGAGGGCCUGGACACUCUGAGCGGACAGCCGGGGGGUGGGGGGCGGGACGGGGGUGGCCUGGCCCCCCCGCCAGGCAGCUGUAGCCCCAGCCUCAGCCCCAGCUCCAACAGAAGCAGCCCGGCCACCCACUCCCCGUGACCGCCCACGCCACAUGGACACAGCCCUCGCCCUCCGCCCCGGCUUUUCUCUGCCUUUCUACCGACCAUGUGACCCCGCACCAGCCCUGCCCCCACCUGCCCUCCCGGGCAGUACUGGGGACCUUCCCUGGGGGACGGGGAGGGAGGAGGCAGCGACUCCUUGGACAGAGGCCUGGGCCCUCAGUGGACUGCCUGCUCCCACAGCCUGGGCUGACGUCAGAGGCCGAGGCCAGGAACUGAGUGAGGCCCCUGGUCCUGGGUCUCAGGAUGGGUCCUGGGGGCCUCGUGUUCAUCAAGACACCCCUCUGCCCAGCUCACCACAUCUUCAUCACCAGCAAACGCCAGGACUUGGCUCCCCCAUCCUCAGAACUCACAAGCCAUUGCUCCCCAGCUGGGGAACCUCAACCUCCCCCCUGCCUCGGUUGGUGACAGAGGGGGUGGGACAGGGGCGGGGGGUUCCCCCUGUACAUACCCUGCCAUACCAACCCCAGGUAUUAAUUCUCGCUGGUUUUGUUUUUAUUUUAAUUUUUUUGUUUUGAUUUUUUUAAUAAGAAUUUUCAUUUUAAGCACAUUUAUACUGAAGGAAUUUGUGCUGUGUAUUGGGGGGAGCUGGAUCCAGAGCUGGAGGGGGUGGGUCCGGGGGAGGGAGUGGCUCGGAAGGGGCCCCCACUCUCCUUUCAUGUCCCUGUGCCCCCCAGUUCUCCUCCUCAGCCUUUUCCUCCUCAGUUUUCUCUUUAAAACUGUGAAGUACUAACUUUCCAAGGCCUGCCUUCCCCUCCCUCCCACUGGAGAAGCCGCCAGCCCCUUUCUCCCUCUGCCUGACCACUGGGUGUGGACGGUGUGGGGCAGCCCUGAAAGGACAGGCUCCUGGCCUUGGCACUUGCCUGCACCCACCAUGAGGCAUGGAGCAGGGCAGAGCAAGGGCCCCGGGACAGAGUUUUCCCAGACCUGGCUCCUCGGCAGAGCUGCCUCCCGUCAGGGCCCACAUCAUCUAGGCUCCCCAGCCCCCACUGUGAAGGGGCUGGCCAGGGGCCCGAGCUGCCCCCACCCCCGGCCUCAGCCACCAGCACCCCCAUAGGGCCCCCAGACACCACACACAUGCGCGUGCGCACACACACAAACACACACACACUGGACAGUAGAUGGGCCGACACACACUUGGCCCGAGUUCCUCCAUUUCCCUGGCCUGCCCCCCACCCCCAACCUGUCCCACCCCCGUGCCCCCUCCUUACCCCGCAGGACGGGCCUACAGGGGGGUCUCCCCUCACCCCUGCACCCCCAGCUGGGGGAGCUGGCUCUGCCCCGACCUCCUUCACCAGGGGUUGGGGCCCCUUCCCCUGGAGCCCGUGGGUGCACCUGUUACUGUUGGGCUUUCCACUGAGAUCUACUGGAUAAAGAAUAAAGUUCUAUUUAUUCUA